AGUGACAACUGGCAAGCGGCGGGGCGGUUGCUCGUUGUCAUUCUGGUAGGCGCUGGUUUCCGGAGGGCUCCGAGUGCUUUGUGAGUAUUCGCAUUUGUUUCUGAGAUGCUGGGAGCACGGUUGGCACUGGUCCCAGUUUCUGGAUGAAGAAACUGAGGCUCUGGGGAUUAAGAUCGUGAACUGUGGGGAGUGGAGGAGGCACAGCUGGAGUGAACUUGGGUGUCCAGGGUUCUGUUUCGUCUCACAGAGGAUGUGCGAGGGUGUAUGUGUGCAUUUGAGAAUGUGUGAGGUUGUGUGUGUUUAAGAAAAUGAGAAUGAGGCUGGGCACAGUGGCUCAUGCCUGUAAUCCCAACACUUUGAGAGGCUGAGCUGGGUGGAUGACUUGAGCCCAGGAGUUCAAGACCAGACUGGGGAACAUGGUGAUGAAACCCUGUCUCUACAAAAAAAUACAAAAAAUUAGCAGGGCAUGGCAAUCCAUGCCUGUAGUCCCAGCUACUUGGGAGGCUGAGGUGGGAGGAUUGCUUGAACCCAGGAGAUAAAGGCUGCAGUGAGCCAUGAUCGCACCACUGCACUCCAGCCUGGGCAACAGAGUGAGACCCUGUCUCCAAAAAAAGAAAGAAAGAAAAUAAAAAGGAGAGAGGUUAGAAAAGGGGGCUGGGCGCGGUGGCUCACGCCUGUAAUCCCAGCACUUUGGGAGGCCGAGGCGGGCGGAUCACGAGGUCAGGAGAUCGAGACCAUCCUGGCUAACACGGUGAAACCCCGUCUCUACUAAAAAAAAAUACAAAAAAUUAGCCGGGCGUGGUAGCGGGCGCCUGUAGUCCCAGCUACUCGGGAGGCUGAGGCAGGAGAAUGGCGUGAGCCCGGGAGGCGGAGCUUGCAGUGAGCCGAGAUCGCGCCACUGCACUCCAGCCUGGGCGACAGAGCAAGACUCCGUCUCAAAAAAAAAAAAAAAAAAAAAGAAAAGAAAAGGGGUAGGCCCCUCAGUAUCACCCUUCCUGAGAACAGUCAUUCUCUGCUUUUUCUGAUCAGAGCUCCCUCCCAGGAGGGGCCCUUUUAUCCAAAGCGAUCUCUGGCCCAGGCACCAAAGAAAGGCCCCAGUGGUUUACGCAGCCGGGCUGCCCCCUGCGCCUGCUGGGUGAGGGGUGGGUCGUGGAAGCCUUCCCCUCCUGCCUGUUCUUUCCUGCUCCUCCCCAGUGCAUCUUUAUAGCUGGCAUAUGGAAACUGUUUCUAUUUAUCUGGCACCACCAGGACGCUGCUGCAUGCUGUGCUCCAGCAAACAGAAACCUUGGAUUCCCUGCAGGGUCAUUUCCGAUGUGGCGUGCAAAGCAGCCAGCUGUUUCGAGGGAGCGUCUGGGCCCUGUGACAUCAGCAUGUGGGAGUGUUACCGUGUGUGCAAACAGAUGGCGGCAGCUAUGCCAUCCACGACUCCCAGGCCCCCAGUCUCAGCUCUGGGGGUGAGAGUUCCCCCUCCAGCCCCGCACACAACUGGGAGAUGAAUUACCAAGAGGCAGCAAUCUACCUCCAGGAAGGCGAGAACAACGACAAGUUCUUCACCCACCCCAAGGAUGCCAAGGCGCUGGCGGCCUACCUCUUUGCACACAAUCACCUCUUCUACCUGAUGGAGCUGGCCACGGCCCUGCUGCUGCUGCUGCUCUCCCUGUGCGAGGCCCCCGCCGUCCCCGCACUCCGGCUUGGCAUCUAUGUCCACGCCACCCUGGAGCUGUUUGCCCUGAUGGUGGUAGUGUUUGAACUCUGCAUGAAGUUACGCUGGCUGGGCCUCCACACCUUCAUCCGGCACAAGCGGACCAUGGUCAAGACCUCGGUGCUGGUGGUGCAGUUUGUCGAGGCCAUCGUGGUGUUGGUACGGCAGAUGUCCCAUGUGCGGGUGACCCGAGCACUGCGCUGCAUUUUCCUGGUGGACUGUCGGUAUUGCGGUGGCGUCCGGCGCAACCUGCGGCAGAUCUUCCAGUCCCUGCCGCCCUUCAUGGACAUCCUCCUGCUGCUGCUGUUCUUCAUGAUCAUCUUUGCCAUCCUCGGUUUCUACUUGUUCUCCCCUAACCCUUCAGACCCCUACUUCAGCACCCUGGAGAACAGCAUCGUCAGUCUGUUUGUCCUUCUGACCACAGCCAAUUUCCCAGAUGUGAUGAUGCCCUCCUACUCCCGGAACCCCUGGUCCUGCGUCUUCUUCAUCGUGUACCUCUCCAUCGAGCUGUAUUUCAUCAUGAACCUGCUUCUGGCUGUGGUGUUCGACACCUUCAAUGACAUUGAGAAACGCAAGUUCAAGUCUUUGCUACUGCACAAGCGAACCGCUAUCCAGCAUGCCUACCGCCUGCUCAUCAGCCAGAGGAGGCCUGCCGGCAUCUCCUACAGGCAGUUUGAAGGCCUCAUGCGCUUCUACAAGCCCCGGAUGAGUGCCAGGGAGCGCUAUCUUACCUUCAAGGCCCUGAAUCAGAACAACACACCCCUGCUCAGCCUAAAGGACUUUUACGAUAUCUACGAAGUUGCUGCUUUGAAGUGGAAGGCCAAGAAAAACAGAGAGCACUGGUUUGAUGAGCUUCCCAGGACGGCGCUCCUCAUCUUCAAAGGUAUUAAUAUCCUUGUGAAGUCCAAGGCCUUCCAGUAUUUCAUGUACUUGGUGGUGGCAGUCAACGGGGUCUGGAUCCUCGUGGAGACAUUUAUGCUGAAAGGUGGGAACUUCUUCUCCAAGCACGUGCCCUGGAGUUACCUCGUCUUUCUAACUAUCUAUGGGGUGGAGCUGUUCCUGAAGGUUGCCGGCCUGGGCCCUGUGGAGUACUUGUCUUCCGGAUGGAACUUGUUUGACUUCUCCGUGACAGUGUUCGCCUUCCUGGGACUGCUGGCGCUGGCCCUCAACAUGGAGCCCUUCUAUUUCAUCGUGGUCCUGCGCCCCCUCCAGCUGCUGAGGUUGUUUAAGUUGAAGGAGCGCUACCGCAACGUGCUGGACACCAUGUUCGAGCUGCUGCCCCGGAUGGCCAGCCUGGGCCUCACCCUGCUCAUCUUUUACUACUCCUUCGCCAUCGUGGGCAUGGAGUUCUUCUGCGGGAUCGUCUUCCCCAACUGCUGCAACACGAGUACAGUGGCAGAUGCCUACCGCUGGCGCAACCACACCGUGGGCAACAGGACCGUGGUGGAGGAAGGCUACUAUUAUCUCAAUAAUUUUGACAACAUCCUCAACAGCUUUGUGACCCUGUUUGAGCUCACAGUUGUCAACAACUGGUACAUCAUCAUGGAAGGCGUCACCUCUCAGACCUCCCACUGGAGCCGCCUCUACUUCAUGACCUUUUACAUUGUGACCAUGGUGGUGAUGACGAUCAUUGUCGCCUUUAUCCUCGAGGCCUUCGUCUUCCGAAUGAACUACAGCCGCAAGAACCAGGACUCGGAAGUUGAUGGUGGCAUCACCCUUGAGAAGGAAAUCUCCAAAGAAGAGCUGGUUGCCGUCCUGGAGCUCUACCGGGAGGCACGGGGGGCCUCCUCGGAUGUCACCAGGCUGCUGGAGACCCUCUCCCAGAUGGAGAGAUACCAGCAACAUUCCAUGGUGUUUCUGGGACGGCGAUCAAGGACCAAGAGCGACCUGAGCCUGAAGAUGUACCAGGAGGAGAUCCAGGAGUGGUAUGAGGAGCAUGCCAGGGAGCAAGAGCAGCAGCGACAACUCAGCAGCAGUGCAGCCCCCGCCGCCCAGCAGCCCCCAGGCAGCCGCCAGCGCUCCCAGACCGUUACCUAGCCCAGCGCCCGAAAGCCGUCUCUUCUAUGCAAUAACACAAUAGUAUUACUCUACUGCGAUGUACGGAACUGCGGUGUGUGUACACAUACUCACGUAUAUGCACAUAUUUAUAUACAGGAAGAAAAAAGACAGACAAGAUGGGGCUUGGUUUAUAACCACCUUGCCCUGUCUUCCUUAACUCCAGAAGCCAGUUUGGUGAGGGGUGGGGGUGCGGCCACCAGGUCUGAGCUCUUCCUACUGUGGAAGGCUCCAGAAGGCCCUUCACAAGGAGACCCCUCACCUGGAUCCAGUCGACUGCGGGGCUUGCCCCUCAUGUGGGCUGGCCUCCAUCGGCCACGUCCAAAGCUGUCACUGCUACUGCUUCAGGCUCACAUCCCCCCGACCUGAUGGCGUGCCCGCCCCCUCUCCCUGCGGCCCAUGCCACAGGUUUCUGUGUUUUGCUUUAGGGACAGAACCACUUAGGAAGGAAAGAACUCCCGGUCUCCAGGGUGGUAUUUCAGUGUCUGUGAUAAUGUCACGCAACACCUCUUCGGGGACCAGUGCCCAGGAUCUAAUGGAAGCGGAAUUGGGGCAACUGGGCCCAUGUGGCCAGAGCUCAGUUAGCCAGUGCCGGGCGGCCACAGAUUACACUGACCAAUCUCCUCCCUUGGCUCUGCAAGCCUCCCACCCAGCCUUCUCUGGCUUAACCCUUGUUGGCGAAAACUCUUCCACAGUGGCCUCCUUGGGGACCCAGAACCCGGAGGAAGGGGCAUGAGGCAGGAAGUGGGGCCGAUGUCUGCAACCCAGACCACUUCGUGGAAUGGGCUCUUGACCAAAUCCCUUUUUUUGCGAUUUACCCGUUCAAGCAAAACAACGUUUUGGUUAACUAAGGAUUGUGCUAAAGCCGAUACCAGGUCCUUCACACGUGUGCACUAGGAACAGGAGCGAACAGCACAGAGAGACGCUCCCUGUGGGACGCAGCAGCCCCGUGGCCCCGGCCCAGUUCCCAGCCACCCUCCCUGGCUCUGCUCACACCAGAGAUUUCCAUAGCAGGAGCGGUUGGUGCAGAAGUAGGUUCAGAUGAACCUCAGUUAACGUCGCCACCCCUCCUCCCACCAUGGUACCCUGUAGGAGCCCUGUAUGACAUCUGAGCGUGGUGGAGGUAGGAGGGUUGCCAGCUGCAGUGACCCUGCCACAGAGGCAGGGUCAGUGCAGAGGUCGCUUUGGUUCCGCUUCCCUGGGCCACAGAACGGAACACAGCAUAGGUUCUGCAGCAGGAGCCGCAGUGGCAGGAUGGAGGGUGCGAAGGGCAAGGAGUGCACUGCUGGGCAUUCCUGGCCAGCCCCGGCCCUCUGGUGCCUGCUUCCUGUGACUUCAGAAGGCAGGUGGACAGAGCCUCCCUCUGGCCUUGUCCUCUUCCCAGCCACAGAACGGGCAGGGUGGCACCCGACCCCAGGGGAGCAGUACCUGGUCCCCCACCCCCUCCUCCCAACCACCUCCAAGGCCAAGCUGGGUCCCAUAGCCAGCACGGCAUGGUUCUCCCCUUCCCCCCUUCCCAGGUCAGGGGAGUUGGACAAGUAGCAGGUGUUUGUUUUUAAAGCACAGCCCUUUGGGAAAGCAACACAUUAUUGAGACUCACUGUGAUUCCCCCGGGAGUCAGACUGGCUUUGUCCUCUUCCUCUCUGGAGGGCCAUGGGCCAUCAGCAGGAGCUCCACAUCGAGCCCCAGGCCAGAACCCCCUCCCUUUCACAGAGAGGGAACUUUAUUGCACAAUUGGGUGCCUUUUAGCUUUUGUGUGUUGAAAUGGGCGUUUUGGAAGCAAGGGUCAGGGGACAGCUUCUAAAGGUGUGAGUCUCUGACCUGAGCAUCUGGGCCUCGCCUGGGCCCUUCUUCCUCCCCAGGGGUGGAAACGUGGAGGGGCCAGCAGCACCCCGGGGUCUGCCCAGGGGAGUCAAGGCCCCGAGGUGGGGGGGCCUAUUCCAGGAGGAGUGGGAUCUCGGCCCUGUCCAGAGCGAGUUAAUGUGUCCAUCUGCCCAACCCUGUCCUGAGAAAGGACCUGGUUUUGGCCAGGACCUGACAAAUACCCAAUGGCAGCAGUGUCAACAGACGGGAGUCCAGCCAGGGUGGGUGCCCUUGUCAUUGAGGUUAGGGACAGCUAUCCCCAGGUUAUGCCUGGCCCCACCCAGCAGGGAGUUGGGGUCCCCCCACAGGCUGUGAGCUCUGUGGGCCCUGGGAUGUGAUCUAGCUCAGAUGCCCUCUCAUCCUUGAUGUCAUAGUUGAGUGCACCCAAGUGGCACCCACUGGCGGCCAGGGGCACAGCCUGGUGGUGGUGGCAAUAGAACUGUGCCCCUCCUCAGCUCCUCGCUUCCCCUCCCACAGCCCCAGCCUUACUCCACCAUGCGGACAAUCAUUUUGUACGGAUCACGGGAGCAAUGCUGUACGGUUUUGUACACUGGUGGUUUGUUUCCUAGAAAACCCAUUGUGUCUCUGGAUUUCUAGCACAUUACUAAAAGAGCCUCUGCUUUGUAAA